GGGCGGGGCUGCGGACUGGCGCAGCCUGGAGGGAGGCAUCAGGCAGUGGCGGAAAAGGGGCGGAGAACCGGAGAAAAGGGCGGAGAACCGGAGAAAAGGGCGGAGAACCGGAGAAAAGGGCGGAGAACCGGGAAAAGGGCGGAGAACCGGGAAAAGGUCAAGACCUCUCACUUUGAGUUUCUUUACCUGUAAUUCCUGAUGGAGAUUCCCUAAAUGAGAAUAGUGCUGAAGACUAACAGUUAAUCACAUCUCUUCUUAGGGGGAAGAGAUAAAAAGGGCUGGGAAGCCAAUUAAAAAAAUAGGUCCAAUUUCAGUGUUUACUCCUCUGAAAGUCCUGCUCAUUGCAAAGUUUGGCAUACGAAGGAGGACUUGGAACUCGUUGAAUGCCAGGGACAACAGGGAAAAAGACCUCAAAAAACAAAACAGCAAUAUAAUAAUGAAUUCUACUCUCAUUUCAUACAUUUAAACAUUAAAUGGUAACAAUAGUCAUUAAUAUAGUUAUAAAACCAUAAAAUAAUAUUUCCAGUAUAAUUUAAAAUUCCGAAUACCUAAGCGAAAAGUACAACUUCUGCUUGUCUCAUAUUAACUCCAGUUUCAAAAAGGGCCCUUUUAUUGCAGUGCUGGUGUCAAGGUACACCAGAUUUCUACCGGCAGGGUCAGGCUCUAUUAUGAAAGUGCCUUGGAAGACAAAACUGUGCUGAACAAACACGAAACACCAGUGUUGUUCACCAGGUGUGUUGUUGCCCCUUUUGGAAGUGUGGUCAAGUAUUUAAUAGCAUUUGACUAAUAUAUAUUCAUCCAUAAUGAAAGCCAGACACUUUAUGAAAAGUUCACUUUAUUCUUUGUGAAUGGACACGUUAUUUAGCCUCUUCGUGCCUCAGCUCCCUCAGCUGAAAAGUGAGAAUAUAACGACACUUAACUGCUUUAUAGGGUUAAAGUGAGGAUUAAGUGGGAUAAUUCAUGCAAAUCUCUAAGAACAGUGCCUGACAUACAAAAAGCGCUAAACAUGUUGCCAAUUAUUAACUUCACAAAAAUAUCUACAGUGGAGCGGCAGUUCCGAGUUCUAUUGAGGUCUAGUGUAAGAUACAUCUCUCACAGUAUCUUGUAAAUUUUUGAUUCUACCAUCAUCAAAACUAGCUCAAUUAAUGUAUCAGUUCGGUCAUCUCAAGAACAUUUAUUAAACCCUCACUCUGGUUACAUCUUGUAUCAGGGAAUUAGUUGAUUUUAAUCCAGUGCUUUGGUUUUCACUGGAGGAAAAAAGUUCACAGCGUUAUUAAGUCCCAGAUAUUUGCCAGGUGUUCAGAGUUUUAGAAAGCUUAUUGUCAGAGACUAAACUAAGAAGGCUUUUGAAGGCGCUCAGAUCAGGUGGGAAAGUGAGAAGGGCUGGUAUUGUGUUCCGAGUAUGUCAAGAAGGAGCUCCUGGCCUGGGCCUAUUGAUGGGCGUUUAGAACCCUCCUGGGCAUUAUUUCUAGCUGGCGGCUGAAUAAGAGGCAAGAGUCACCCUCUUUUUGAGUUAAAUCACGUGCUUAAUUAAAAGUGAAGGUGGCGGCGGCCUCAGCGCCCUCCCCCUCCGUGCUGCUGGCUUCUUCCCAACGGUGUUCUGGCCACGUCCUGCGCCUUCUCGCGCACGGGAGAGCGCUCUGGGUAGAGGCCGGGCCCGGGCAGCAGGUGGCCCCAGGUAGCUCAGUGGCGUGGCAGUCUCCUUCUCGCCCGGUCCGGAGCGGAGGGGAGCGGCUCAGGUGCCGGCUCGGGGGAGGCCCGGGCACCUCGGGGAUCCAGAGCCCGCUGGCGCCGCGCCCGGGAGGGCACCACCGGCGAGGACGAAGCCGCGCCUCCUCCCGGAACUGGCCGGCGCCGCGAGGCGGGAGGAGCAGCGGGAGCCGGGCAGCCGCGCGCCGGGGACCAUGGACGUCCUUCCCACCGGCGGGGGCCGCCCGGGGCUCCGGACGGAGCUGGAAUUCCGCGGCGGCGGUGGCGAGGCGAGGCUGGAGAGUCAGGAGGAAGAAACGAUUCCUGCAGCUCCCCCAGCCCCGCGCCUCCGGGGAGCGGCGGAGCGGCCGCGGCGCUCCCGGGACACGUGGGACGGCGAUGAGGACACGGAGCCCGGCGAGGCGUGCGGCGGCCGCACAAGCCGCACGGCGUCCCUGGUGAGCGGGCUGCUCAACGAGCUGUACAGCUGCACAGAGGAGGAGGAGGCGGCGGGCGGGGGCCGCGGGGCCGAGGGCCGCCGGCGGCGCCGCGACAGCCUCGACAGCUCCACCGAGGCCUCGGGCUCCGACGUGGUCCUGGGCGGCCGCAGCGGUGCCGGCGACUCCCGCGUGCUGCAGGAGCUGCAGGAGCGACCGAGCCAGCGGCAUCAGAUGCUGUACCUGCGGCAGAAAGACGCUAAUGAACUGAAGACGAUCCUUCGAGAGCUAAAGUACAGAAUUGGCAUCCAGUCGGCCAAGUUACUUCGGCAUCUGAAGCAGAAAGAUAGGCUUCUGCAUAAAGUGCAGAGGAACUGUGAUAUUGUGACUGCCUGCUUGCAGGCUGUGUCACAGAAGAGAAGAGUUGAUACCAAGUUGAAAUUCACUCUUGAGCCAUCUUUAGGUCAAAAUGGUUUUCAGCAGUGGUACGAUGCUCUCAAGGCAGUUGCCAGGCUAUCCACAGGAAUACCAAAGGAAUGGAGGAGAAAGGUUUGGUUGACCUUGGCAGAUCAUUAUUUGCACAGUAUAGCCAUUGACUGGGACAAAACCAUGCGCUUCACUUUCAAUGAAAGGAGUAAUCCUGAUGAUGACUCCAUGGGAAUUCAGAUAGUCAAGGACCUUCACCGCACAGGCUGUAGUUCUUACUGUGGCCAGGAGGCUGAGCAGGACAGGGUUGUGUUGAAGCGGGUGCUGCUGGCCUAUGCCCGAUGGAACAAAACUGUUGGGUACUGCCAAGGCUUUAACAUCCUGGCUGCACUAAUUCUGGAAGUGAUGGAAGGCAAUGAAGGGGAUGCCCUGAAAAUUAUGAUUUACCUUAUUGAUAAGGUACUUCCCGAAAGCUAUUUCGUCAAUAAUCUCCGGGCAUUGUCUGUGGAUAUGGCUGUCUUCAGAGACCUUUUAAGAAUGAAGCUGCCGGAAUUAUCUCAGCACCUGGAUACUCUUCAGAGAACUGCAAACAAAGAAAGUGGAGGUGGAUAUGAGCCCCCACUUACAAAUGUCUUCACGAUGCAGUGGUUUCUGACUCUCUUUGCCACAUGCCUCCCUAAUCAGACCGUUUUAAAGAUCUGGGAUUCAGUCUUCUUUGAAGGUUCAGAAAUCAUCCUAAGGGUGUCGCUGGCUAUCUGGGCAAAAUUAGGAGAGCAGAUAGAAUGUUGUGAAACAGCAGAUGAAUUCUACAGCACCAUGGGGCGCCUUACCCAGGAGAUGCUAGAGAAUGAUCUUCUGCAAAGCCAUGAACUCAUGCAGACUGUUUAUUCCAUGGCUCCGUUCCCUUUCCCACAAUUGGCAGAGUUGAGGGAAAAAUACACCUACAACAUUACACCGUUCCCAGCCACAGUUAAACCCACCUCAGUUUCUGGACGACAUAGUAAGGCCAGAGACAGUGAUGAAGAGAAUGACCCAGACGAUGAGGAUGCUGUCGUUAAUGCAGUGGGGUGUCUUGGACCUUUUAGUGGGUUCCUGGCUCCUGAACUGCAGAAGUACCAAAAACAAAUUAAAGAGCCAAAUGAGGAGCAGAGUCUGAGAUCUAAUAACAUUGCAGAGCUGAGUCCAGGAGCAAUCAAUUCCUGUCGAAGUGAAUACCAUGCAGCUUUUAACAGUAUGAUGAUGGAACGCAUGACCACAGAUAUCAAUGCACUGAAGCGGCAGUACUCUCGAAUUAAAAAGAAGCAACAGCAGCAGGUUCAUCAGGUGUACAUCAGGGCAGGCUCUAAAGAAGAAAAAGACUGCAGGUUCUUUUUAGGCCCCAAGGACCAGGCAGUUGAUGACAAAGGGCCAGUGACCAGCAUUCUCCCGUCUCAGGUAAACAGUUCUCCAGUUAUAAACCACCUUCUUUUAGGAAAGAAGAUGAAAAUGACUAACAGAGCUGCCAAGAAUGCUGUCAUCCACAUCCCUGGUCACACAGGAGGGAAAAUAUCUCCUGUCCCCUACGAAGACCUUAAGACGAAGCUCAACUCCCCGUGGCGAACUCACAUCCGAGUCCACAAAAAGAACAUGCCAAGGACCAAGAGUCAUCCGGGCUGUGGGGACACCGUAGGGCUGAUAGAUGAGCAGAACGAGGCCAGCAAGACCAAUGGGCUGGGGGCAGCAGAGGCAUUCCCCUCUGGUUGUACAGCGACAGCUGGGAGAGAAGGCAGCAGCCCUGAAGGCAGUACCAGGAGGACGAUCGAGGGGCAGUCUCCGGAGCCGGUGUUCGGAGAUGCUGAUGUGGAUGUGUCUGCAGUUCAGGCGAAGUUGGGAGCCCUGGAACUGAACCAGAGGGAUGCUGCAGCUGAAACUGAGCUCAGGGUGCACCCACCCUGCCAGCGGCACUGCCCAGAGCCGCCGAGUGCACCCGAAGAAAACAAAGCCACCAGCAAAGCUCCCCAAGGCAGCAACUCAAAAACCCCCAUCUUUAGCCCUUUUCCCAGCGUCAAGCCCCUGCGGAAAUCUGCUACUGCCAGGAACUUGGGAUUAUAUGGCCCUACAGAAAGAACCCCAACUGUGCACUUUCCUCAAAUGAGUAGGAGCUUCAGCAAACCCGGCGGUGGAAACAGUGGCACUAAAAAACGAUGAUGUCUCCCCGAAACUUUGUAUCUGGACUCACCUUUUCACAGUAGUAUAAGGGUUGCAGCUGAAUGGCUCUAAAAGAGUUUUAUUUGUCCAGUGAAAAUGAAUAGGUUCAGGGAUGAGCAACAGCCCAUAAAAAAUGGGAACUGGAAGUUUUAUAAUAGGAGUUAGAACAGGGCUGUUUUCCCAGCUACUUGCUAACUGACGAAGUGGAUUCUUGUGGCAAAAUAAAUAUUGUGGUUUUAUAGUGUGAAGUUUUCCCAAUUUUUCAUUGUGAGCUGUUUAAAAAAGACUAUAUCUAGAUUGUUAACUCUCGUCCAUCCUUCUGUUCUGGGGGCCUUCAGAGUCCCUGUGACAGCACCCCCAAACCUUCCAGUUCUCUGGGUGUUACUAAUACUCAAGCAUGCACAUACCAGCUUGCUAGGACAGAAACUGUAAAAAGAAAGUAAGUUUCUUCGUUACAAAAAACUUCCUGAUUUUCCUUUUCAUGCUUUACGGAGGGGAUUGUGUCGUGUGAGAUUUCCCACAGUACCAGUUUCAAAUUUUUUUUUUAUUCUUAUGCUAAAUCAUAGGAGAAAAAUCUAGAUAGCCUUUCUUUAACUGUCUAUUUCUACCUGCAAAAUGAAGAAAACCUUUCAUCUGUUGAAAUUUCAAUCGAUAACCCAGCUGAAGAUCUUAUGCACAGGACACACUUGGCAUAUGCUUUACGCAGUUGCUCCGGACAGCUUGCUCGCGCCACUGAGCUUUUCCUGAGGUUUGUGUUCGCCUCUCAAGGAGAGCUUUGAUCCUCAGUGGUACGGAUGACUUGAUGGGCUCCAUGCGGAGCCUGGCCUGCAUCCCCCACCACACAGCUCACUCACCCACCAGCUCUAGACUGCAGACGCACAAGGCCUCUGCUCAGAAGCCAGAACACAGCACCUGUGACUCUGUUACUUGAAUUUUGUGCUUUUUGAUUGGAGUCCUUUGUUGAGUACUUUGUUAAUUGAACACUGCCUUUCUCUGGAGAAGGCCCCAGUGCUUUCUAGCUCCCUCUCACUCCUGCCCUUUCUAGCUCUCUCUCACCCAGCGGGUCAGGGAUAGCACCUCUUGUCUCCACUAUGCAGAUGGGAACUCUGAGCCACACAGAGGUGAAGUAGCACUUCAGUUACUCAAGGUCAGUACUCUCGGUAUUCCAAGUGACUUAGCCACAUUUCCUUCAGUGCAAUAGGUGGGUUUAAUGCUCUUUGUACACAGAUGUAUUGGCUACAUAGCGUGUAAAAACCAAGACUGGGAAGCCAUUCACUAAAAUCCCUCCUGACUCAAAGGACCUGUCUCCAGAUGGUACAGAGUCCCUUGAUGGCAUUUUACAAAACCAGCUCUGACUUCCUUAUCCUGAACAGGGAGUUUAUUUUAAAAAUGCUUCAUGCACCUGUUAUUUGGCUGAACAGAAGGCUCACUCCUCAAUCCCCUUCUCCUCGCCAUCAUUAGAGGAAUAGACUCAGCCUUCAUGUUUGUCUCUGGAAGACGAUUGGCGAUACUUGCAGGAAUAUUGUUGAUGCAGCCAAUAUUAAUUUGAGCUAAUGGAUUGUUAAUUCUGAAACGAAAACUGUAACUGUAGAGCAGGCUUUUACUAUGAGAGGUACUACUUUUUAUAAUAGAGAAUGUGGUUGUGUGGGCUUUUUUUGAACAGAAAACACAACAAUGACCUAUACCGUGAGAAAAGCCAUUUUAUCUUCUUCGUGGUAUUUUUACCCCCAAAGGAACUGAAGAUGGAAAAUAUGACUAAUAAGUUAUUGCAGUUUUGGUCUUGAAUUCUGUGCCAUCUGAAGUUAGCAUCCAGCUUCUUAAAAAGCAGCCACGCCUACAGCCUGUUUUUUGGGAAGGCUGUAGGUGGAGAGAUGGGCUUAUUUUGCAUACCACCCUCAGGGCCCAGAGACCCACUGCAUUUUCCAAAGUUAAGCAAAUGACACCAUUUUCUUCCAUCAGCUAAACUUUACAGAUAAUAGUGUUUCCACCUCAUAUCCUUUUCUUUGCCCCUUCUCAAAUGAGUCAGAAUAGUCAUGUUCCCCUUGAGGGAUGUCUGACUUGAAUGGAGAAUUGUUCUUUCCUCUCUUGAAUCAGCUCACUAGCUCCCUGAUGGUCUGGGUUCAAGGAAAUGGUUAAUGAGGUAGAGGCCACUUAUACAAGUCCUUGGGAUUGUACCAUUGCUGUCCACAAACUUAGUAUCAACAACACAUGCUGUGCCCUGUGAACACUCUCCUCUCACCUAUUUCCAGGGUUGGUCUUCCUGAGAAGGGGAUGGAUGAGGUAACACACAGUUUGGGAUACGUAUCUGUUGAAUGAAUGAAUAAGUGAAAGGAUAAUAGUCCUCUGAGGUAAAAAUGGCCUUGUCAGAAUUUUGAAAAUCCAACAGAUUCCUAUUAAAGCACUCUGUGUACCAAUAACAUGCAUGCAUUGUACCAAGUAAUCACAAUGUGAAUUGGUCAAUUUAUGAGCCUUGCCUACUUUAGAAAAUAAAGAAACCUGCAGUAGCCUCUACCACACAGCAUGUACAAAGACCAGUAUGGACUUGCUAUCUUCCCUAUGUAUUGGACACUGUAUGCAAACACCAGAAGUACUUAACAAGUAGUGGUUUCUUGAUUUUUAGAUAUGUCUGUAGCCUCUUAGCCCUUUUGCCGGGAAUCAACUCAUUCUGAUGCCUCUGCACCUCAGUUCCUCUUACAAAAGCCUCCAGAUGAUCUAAAUCUAGUUAGCAAUGUCAGCCUGUGGACUGCAGCUGUUUGGGACAUUGUAUUCCUUUGUUUGUCUCUUGUUGUUCUGAAGGAUUGUAUUGAUCACAAAGCUAUAUGCAUAAAGAUUCUCAUUGUUGUAACUGUUCUGCCAUUUUCUGAGUGCAAGCAUGGAACACUGUUGUGACAGUCCCUUCUCCCUUCUUCCUUCUUCCUUCACCCCCAACCCCAGACCCCCCUUGGUCACAUGAACCAGGGAAACAGCCCAAUAAGCUCUAUCUCCCCCAGUCUAAUCGCUGGGUUGCAGGGUGGCCUGUGACCUGCCCAGCAUUUGCAGACUCGCUGGUUCCUGAAUAUGAGUAAGCACAGAGUUUACCUAGAGAGUUUACCUAAAAUUAACCUUUAGAUCUACUAUUUAUUUUUGUCUUAAUAAAAUGAACAAUAAAUAUAGUUUAGCUGCAUGGCAUUAAGGAUUCUGUAUGAAUAGAUGUAUAGUUGCUGCCAUCUCCCCAUAUAAAAACUCUCUUUACAUCGUUUCUGAGCCACUUUCUUUGCUGUCUGCAGCAUUUAAAAUAUAUUAUUUUUCCUAAUUAGAAAAGUCACAGGUUUUAGAAAAUUGGGAAAACAAAAAGAGCAUAAAGAAUCAUCAAUACUCUGAUAUAGAUAUAGAUCUUUCCAGUACGUUUGUGUAUGUGUGUACACGCCAUUAUCUACAAAAAAGUUAUGUUGAACAUGGUAGUUUAAGCUGUCUUUCUGGUAAAUGCUCUUAUACAAUAUGAUUUUUAGUGACUAAUAUUCCCUAAUGUGUUCAUGCCAGAAUUCACAUAACCAGUACCUUGUCAAAUAGGAGGUUUCUGAUUAGAUAGUAGUAGAGACAGUAUCCUGUUACAUGUAUGUACAUAGCCCGAAUUAUUUUCUUAGGAUAUGCGUAUAGAAGUGGAGUUGAAGGGUCAGGAAAUAUGUCCAUUUUUAAGAUACAUAUAUCUCCAAAUUGCCAUUCUUAAAGGUUGGAGUUAUACAAGUAGUGAAUGAGAAUGCCUGCUUCUCUACAUCCUGGAAGAGGCAGCAGUCUCUUUCCUUUUUUUUCCUUUCUAUGACUUCUAGUGUGGAAGUGCCAACAGAAGUGUUUUAGAAGCAGUGAUAAUGAACACUCAUAACACCCAUACCUCAUUCCUGACUUUUAAAAGAAGCAUUAAGUAAGAUGUUGAGGUUUCUGGUAGGUGCCUAUUAUUAGGUUAAGAAAAUUCCCUUUUAUUCUUUGCUUGCUAAGAGUUUUCUUCAUCAACAGGUAUUGAAUUUCAUAAAAAGAACUUUAAUUGUAUCUUUUGAGAAGGGAAUAGUACUUGAGACUUGGUAUCCUGAACUCAAAGAAAUAGCCAUUACUAGGUUUUGUCAAAGAAUACCAGAUAUUUUAGAGUUGGAAGUUAUGCAGUAAAAGCUUUAUGUGCAAAUGUUCAUUGAAGUAUUAAAUGUACUAAUGGAAACCUGAAAACAAUAUAAACAUCUGGGAAUAGGGGAGAUGUUUGGAUGAAUUAUGAUUCAUCCCCAGGAUGGAAAUGUGAAGGCCGGUGAGUAUUUGGACCAUUGAAGUGGGAGUUAUCUGUUAUCCACAUCAGGCAGCUCAGAGUAAAGUCAGCAAGUCUACAGUCAUAGAGCCACCAGGAUACAGUGAUGGAUGGGAGGCCUUUGCUGGACAGUGGCUGAAGGCAGAACUGUUGGAGUGGUUCUUCCACAAAGGCAGCCAGUGCUCACCUGAAUGGGGACUGGUACUGUAGGUAUUGGGUCAGCUUUCAUGCCGUUCCCUGCUGGCCAUCUCCCAAUGCUGAAUGUCUGACUCAGUUCAGGCUGCUGUAACAAAGUACCAUAGACUGAGGUGGCUUAAACACAGACAUUUCUUUCUCACAGUUCUGGAGGCUGAGAAGUCAAAGAUCAACGUGUCUGCAAAUUUGGUAUCUGGUGAGGAAGGGCCCUCUUCCUGGUUUGCAGAUGGCUACCUUCUCACUGUGUCCUCACACAAUGGAGAAAGGGAGUAUGUUUUGGUCUCUUCCUCUUCUGAUAAGGGCACUAACCUCAUCAUGAGGGUCCCAUCCUCCUGGUGUCAUCUAAACCUAAUUACCUCCCAAUGGCCCCGCCUUCAAAUACCAUCACGUUGAAGGUUGCUUCCUUCCUGGUCGUUUGCUCUGGUGAGACCAAAUGACCUGCAAAGUGUCACUUGAUUCCAUUCUCUCCAUCCCUUCCAUCCCAGGCAAUCUUUAUCUAGCUACACCAACCUGUGCCCCAGGGGCUUCAAGAGUUGUUGUUGUUUUAACAUUAAAAAACCAGAAAGUUCACUUGUUUCUUAGUGUUUACAUCCUUGCUAUAACAAUUCUAGUUUUCCUUUAGGCAAUGCUGAUCACUGGGAAGGAGGUGGAUCAAUUCUCCUAUGGGACCAACAGUUUUCUGGGAAGAAACUUCCUGAUACCUCAGCCUAGGAAUCUCCCUAUCCCUGGAGAGUCCAGGAAUCUAUAUUAAAACAUGAAACAAAGCAAAAAAUAAAAAAAAAC